GGGCGGCUGGCCGGGCAGAGGGGCUCCUUGUGAGCUUGUGAGGAACUUUCUACUUAAGAAUGACCAAGUGGCCUUGUGGGAAGGAAGAGGGUUGCCAUUUGUUAAUGGUGUUUAUAAAUUGCUAUUGGAUUAGUAUAAGCUGCAAAGCAGCUACUAAUUUAUUUUCUUUAACUAGGAGAAUCAUAAUAUGGACAUUUUGGAUAGGCAUCUUUUUAAUUUUCUAAAGAUUUCCAAAAUUGGUAAUGUUAUUUCUAAUUAGGAAGUUUGGUUGAAAAUAAGUUUCUGAACUCUGUGUCAAAUCUAGUAGCUACUUCCAAUUUGUAAUUAAAAAAAGAAAAAGUCUUCAAAGGUUGAAUGUGCCUUCAUGGAUUCUCCAGCAUGAGCAAACUGAAGUAUCCAAAACUGAAUUAAAAAUUUCAUCUAAAUUAUACCUUCUUCUUAGCUUUACUAUACUUAGUGUCAAACUGAUUUCUUAGAUUUCGUAGUCACUUAGUUUUGAAACCUUGAUUCCUUUCCUCUUCGUCACUUCUACGUCUAGUCAGUUAUUUGUUGAAUGCCAUGUAUGUGUAAAGCAGUUUCAGAUUUCACUCCUGUGAGUUCUAUUUCCAUUGCUAUUGGAUGCCUAGUGAGGAAAGCUCCUUUUCUCAUAUCUACCUGUACAAUUUUACUUGUGGGUUUUUUUUUUUUUUGAGACAGAGUCUCGCUCUGUUGCCAGGCUGGAGUGCAGUGGCGCAAUCUCAGCUCACUGCAACCUCCGACUCCCUGGUUCAAGCAAUUUUCCUGCCUCAGCCUCCUGAGUAGCUGGGAUUACAGGCACACGCCACCACGCCCAGCUAAUUUUGUUUUGUAUUUUUAGUAGAGACGGGGUUUCAUGAUGUUGGCCAGGAUGGUCUCAAACUCCUGACCUCGUGAUCCACCCGCCUCGGCCUCCCAAAGUGCUGGGAUUACAGGCGUGAGCCACCACGCCUGGCCAGAGCCAGGUUAACUACUAAGUCUUCCUCCUGAAAACCUUACUUUGUUCCUCUAGUUGUAAGUGGCCUUUGCCAUUGUACCACUCUGGUGGUGCUGAGUUCUGACAUGUAUUAUAUAGAUCUCUGCAUGUGACACCCCCAUCCCAAUCUUUUUUUUUUUUUUUUUGAGACAGAAUCUCACUCUGUUGCCCGGUCUGGAGUGCACUGGCACAAUCUUGGUUCACUGCAACCUCCAUAUCCCAGGUUCAAGCGAUUCUCCUGCCUCAACCUCCUGAGUAACUGGGAUUACAGGCCUGCGCCAUCACACCCGGCUAAUUUUUUUGUAUUUUUAGUAGAGACGGGGUUUCACCAUUUUGGCCAGGCUGGUCUCGAACUCCUGACCUCAGGUGAUCUCCCCACCUCAGCCUCCCAGAGUGCUGGGAUUUUAGAUGUGAGCCACCACGCCUGGGUCCUUUCCCCAAUCUUACAGAAGUGUAUGCUGACUUGUAAAGUGAAGAAGCCAGUGGUGCUGCGGGUGUUCUUUUGGGGUAGUGUCUGGGAUCCAGUACGAGUUGAAUCAUUGUUCAAAUAAGGUGUAAUUGAAAAGUGAUCCUCUCUUCAGAGAUGUCAAAAACAAACAAAUCCAAGUCUGGAUCUCGCUCUUCUCGCUCAAGAUCUGCAUCAAGAUCUCGUUCUCGUUCAUUUUCGAAGUCUCGGUCCCGAAGCCGAUCUCUCUCUCGUUCAAGGAAGCGCAGGCUGAGUUCUAGGUCUCGUUCCAGAUCAUAUUCUCCAGCUCAUAACAGAGAAAGAAACCACCCAAGAGUAUAUCAGAAUCGGGAUUUCCGAGGUCACAACAGAGGCUAUAGAAGGCCCUAUUAUUUCCGUGGGCGUAACAGAGGCUUUUAUCCAUGGGGCCAAUAUAACCGAGGAGGCUAUGGAAACUACCGCUCAAAUUGGCAGAAUUACCGGCAAGCAUACAGUCCUCGUCGAGGCCGUUCAAGAUCCCGGUCCCCAAAGAGAAGGUCCCCUUCACCAAGGUCCAGGAGCCAUUCUAGAAACUCUGAUAAGUCGUCUUCUGACCGGUCAAGGCGCUCCUCAUCCUCCCGUUCUUCCUCCAACCAUAGCCGAGUUGAAUCUUCUAAGCGCAAGUCUGCAAAGGAGAAAAAGUCCUCUUCUAAGGAUAGCCGGCCAUCUCAGGCUGCCGGGGAUAACCAGGGAGAUGAGGCCAAGGAGCAGACAUUCUCUGGAGGCACCUCUCAAGAUACAAAAGCAUCUGAGAGCUCGAAGCCAUGGCCAGAUGCCACCUACGGCACUGGUUCUGCAUCACGGGCCUCAGCAGUUUCUGAGCUGAGUCCUCGGGAGCGAAGCCCAGCUCUCAAAAGCCCCCUCCAGUCUGUGGUGGUGAGGCGGCGGUCACCCCGUCCUAGCCCCGUGCCAAAACCUAGUCCUCCACUUUCCAGCACAUCCCAGAUGGGCUCAACUCUGCCGAGUGGUGCCGGGUAUCAGUCUGGGACACACCAAGGUCAGUUCGACCAUGGUUCUGGGUCCCUGAGUCCAUCCAAAAAGAGCCCUGUGGGUAAGAGUCCACCAUCCACUGGCUCCACAUAUGGCUCAUCUCAGAAGGAGGAGAGUGCUGCUUCAGGAGGAGCAGCCUAUACAAAGAGGUAUCUAGAAGAGCAGAAGACAGAGAAUGGAAAAGAUAAGGAACAGAAACAAACAAAUACCGAUAAAGAAAAAAUAAAAGAGAAAGGGAGCUUCUCUGACACAGGCUUGGGUGAUGGAAAAAUGAAAUCUGAUUCUUUUGCUCCCAAAACUGAUUCUGAGAAGCCUUUUCGGGGCAGUCAGUCUCCCAAAAGGUAUAAGCUCCGAGAUGACUUUGAGAAGAAGAUGGCUGACUUCCACAAGGAGGAGAUGGAUGAUCAAGAUAAGGACAAAGCUAAGGGAAGAAAGGAAUCUGAGUUUGAUGAUGAACCCAAAUUUAUGUCUAAAGUCAUAGGUGCAAACAAAAACCAGGAGGAGGAGAAGUCAGGCAAAUGGGAGGGCCUGGUAUAUGCACCUCCAGGGAAGGAAAAGCAGAGAAAAACAGAGGAGCUGGAGGAGGAGUCUUUCCCAGAGAGAUCCAAAAAGGAAGAUCGGGGCAAGAGAAGCGAAGGUGGGCACAGGGGCUUUGUGCCUGAGAAGAAUUUCCGAGUGACUGCUUAUAAAGCAGUCCAGGAGAAAAGCUCAUCACCUCCCCCAAGAAAGACCUCUGAGAGCCGAGACAAGCUGGGAGCGAAAGGAGAUUUUCCCACAGGAAAGUCUUCCUUUUCCAUUACUCGAGAGGCACAGGUCAAUGUCCGGAUGGACUCUUUUGAUGAGGACCUCGCACGACCCAGUGGCUUAUUGGCUCAGGAACGCAAGCUUUGCCGAGAUCUAGUCCAUAGCAACAAAAAGGAACAGGAGUUUCGUUCCAUUUUCCAGCACAUACAAUCAGCUCAGUCUCAGCGUAGCCCCUCAGAACUGUUUGCCCAACAUAUAGUGACCAUUGUUCACCAUGUUAAAGAGCAUCACUUUGGGUCCUCAGGAAUGACAUUACAUGAACGCUUUACUAAAUACCUAAAGAGAGGAACUGAGCAGGAGGCAGCCAAAAACAAGAAAAGCCCAGAGAUACACAGGAGAAUAGACAUUUCCCCCAGUACAUUCAGAAAACAUGGUUUGGCUCAUGAUGAAAUGAAAAGUCCCCGGGAACCUGGCUACAAGGCUGAGGGAAAAUACAAAGAUGAUCCUGUUGAUCUCCGCCUUGAUAUUGAACGUCGUAAAAAACAUAAGGAGAGAGAUCUUAAACGAGGUAAAUCGAGAGAAUCAGUGGAUUCCCGAGACUCCAGUCACUCAAGGGAAAGGUCAGCUGAAAAAACAGAGAAAACUCAUAAAGGAUCAAAGAAACAGAAGAAGCAUCGGAGAGCAAGAGACAGGUCCAGAUCCUCCUCCUCUUCCUCCCAGUCAUCUCACUCCUACAAAGCAGAAGAGUACACUGAAGAGACAGAGGAAAGAGAGGAGAGCACCACGGGCUUUGACAAAUCAAGACUGGGGACCAAAGACUUUGUGGGUCCAAGUGAAAGAGGAGGUGGCAGAGCUCGAGGAACCUUUCAGUUUCGAGCCAGAGGAAGAGGCUGGGGCAGAGGCAACUACUCUGGGAACAAUAACAACAACAGCAACAACGAUUUUCAAAAAAGAAACCGGGAAGAGGAGUGGGACCCAGAGUACACACCCAAAAGCAAGAAGUAUUACUUGCAUGAUGACCGUGAAGGCGAAGGCAGUGACAAGUGGGUGAGCCGGGGCCGGGGCCGAGGAGCCUUUCCUCGGGGUCGGGGCCGGUUCAUGUUCCGGAAAUCAAGUACCAGCCCCAAGUGGGCCCAUGACAAGUUCAGUGGGGAGGAAGGGGAGAUUGAAGACGACGAGAGUGGGACAGAGAACCGAGAAGAGAAGGACAAUAUACAGCCCACAACCGAGUAGGGGCCACCCUUGACGGGAUUCCUGCCCAGGGGAGAGAGGCGCUGGGAAGAUGGCUGGUGAGGAGCUUAACAGAGGAACCUCAAGAAGAUUCUGAAAAUCCUACCCCCACCCCCCACCAGCCGCACAGAUUGUACUACCGCGAGAGGCAUCCCUGGCGCUGUCUCCCACUGGACAGAGGAGGCUGGCCAUGGGGCCCAGGGGUCAGGCCCAGCUUUUGAGCAGAAUACAACGCAUUGGGCUUUAGCUGUUUUUCUCAUUUGUUGGUGUGUGGGGUGGGGGCAGGGGUAGGGCGGGAGAGCGAUGCUUGGAUUUUUGUUUCCUAUUAGAAACCAACAGUUUUGUUCUAAUUUCAUUUCAUUUGGAGCUAAGAUGACUAAUUUGAUGAUUUUCGAUCUCUUUUCCCCUGUCCUGAUUUUAAAAGCCCCCUCCUUUUUUUUUUUUUUUUUCUUUUUUUAGGCAUAUGUAGUAAUAUUAGAAACAUUUAAUUUGGGAAACUUUGAUUCUUGAAAGAGAAAACAAAAGCAUGUGAAUAAACUUUGAAGUGUUCACCUCAGUUUGGGACCAAACUGCUUGGAUCUUUGUAAAAACCGGUUUUGUAUGUCAAGGAGGAGUUUAAGGCCUUUCCGACCACCUUGUGUUCCCCUUUUCUGCGCAGCCAUGUAUCACGUGGAGUUGCUCCUUACCACACCUCACGUGCCCCUGAGCCCUAUUUCCUGAUUUCUUCUGGGCUGGACUUCCCCGUUCUCCACCAGCAGCUCCAGUAUCCCAAACUUUCUAGUCCUGCUGAUCCUCCCAGCAACGGGGUGGAAACUGGAGGGCAGUGUCUGGUCUGUUUUCUAAGAAACUUAUGAAUUCUAUUAUCUUUACAAAUAUGAGAAAAUUUUUUCAAUAUUUUUUAUUAAUCUUUUUAUAAAAUGAAAAGAAACUCCUAUGAUCGAUUAAGGAAGGUGGUUAUGGCUGGGUGGUUCAGGGGUUUUUUUGGGUUUCUUUUUUUUUUUCUUUGUCUUUUUAACCUUAAGCUGUUUAAGUUGAAGCAUUCUCAGAUGUUUGGGGGGAAACAUCCUCUUAAAAUGGGUCCUUGUGCUUGCCUUCUGGGGAGGCGGUCCUGAGCAGGUGAAUCAUAAGGCAUUUAUGCAUAUGUUAUAUGCGGACUGCACCCACCUCUCCCCCCCAGCCUUUGCCUCUUGCGUUGUUGUGCUGCUUUCCCCUUACUUUGCUACAUUUCUAUAGUUAAGUUGGUUUUACUUGAAUGAUUCAUGUUUAGGGGGAAAAUGAAAAUCUCCCUUAAAAUUUGUUUCAACUCCUCCUGCAAAUAAAAUAAAUGAAGUGGCAGAUGUAAA